AGUCUCGUAUCGCGCCCGGGAGGCGCCGGAGCCCAGCGGCUGGCGGUAAGGCCGCCUCCGCGGGGCUGUGGGAAGCUUGGGCUGUCCCAGGACCGUCAGUCUCCUCCUCUGACCCUCCCUUUCCCCUUGUGUGUAGGGCCGCCGUCCCACCCCCACCUCGCCCGAGUCCGGGGCGGCCCCGGUGUCCCCUCCGAGCCUGCUGCACUCCACGUCCCCCUACCAGGGCUCCAGCCCCCAGGGAAAUCUCCGACCAGGCCCGCCCAGGAGCCAGAUCCAGGCUCCUGGAAGAACCAUGUCCGGCAGCUACUGGUCAUGCCAGGCACACACUGCUGCCCAAGAGGAGCUGCUGUUUGAAUUAUCUGUGAAUGUUGGGAAGAGGAAUGCCAGAGCUGCCGGCUGAAAAUUACCCAACCAAGAGAAAUCUGCAGGAUGGACUUUCUGGUCCUCUUCUUGUUCUACCUGGCUUCGGUGCUGAUGGGUCUUGUUCUUAUCUGCGUCUGCUCGAAAACCCAUAGCUUGAAAGGCCUGGCCAGGGGAGGAGCACAGAUAUUUUCCUGUAUAAUUCCAGAAUGUCUUCAGAGAGCCGUGCAUGGAUUGCUUCAUUACCUUUUCCAUACGAGAAACCACACCUUCAUUGUCCUGCACCUGGUCUUGCAAGGGAUGGUUUAUACUGAGUACACCUGGGAAGUAUUUGGCUACUGUCAGGAGCUGGAGUUGUCCUUGCAUUACCUUCUUCUGCCCUAUCUGCUGCUAGGUGUAAACCUGUUUUUUUUCACCCUGACUUGUGGAACCAAUCCUGGCAUUAUAACAAAAGCAAAUGAAUUAUUAUUUCUUCAUGUUUAUGAAUUUGAUGAAGUGAUGUUUCCAAAGAACGUGAGGUGCUCUACUUGUGAUUUAAGGAAACCAGCUCGAUCCAAGCACUGCAGUGUGUGUAACUGGUGUGUGCACCGUUUCGACCAUCACUGUGUUUGGGUGAACAACUGCAUCGGGGCCUGGAACAUCAGGUACUUCCUCAUCUACGUCUUGACCUUGACGGCCUCGGCUGCCACCGUCGCCAUUGUGAGCACCACUUUUCUGGUCCACUUGGUGGUGAUGUCAGAUUUAUACCAGGAGACUUACAUCGAUGACCUUGGACACCUCCAUGUUAUGGACACGGUCUUUCUUAUUCAGUACCUGUUCCUGACUUUUCCACGGAUUGUCUUCAUGCUGGGCUUUGUCGUGGUUCUGAGCUUCCUCCUGGGUGGCUACCUGUUGUUUGUCCUGUAUCUGGCGGCCACCAACCAGACUACUAACGAGUGGUACAGAGGUGACUGGGCCUGGUGCCAGCGUUGUCCCCUUGUGGCCUGGCCUCCGUCAGCAGAGCCCCAAGUCCACCGGAACAUUCACUCCCAUGGGCUUCGGAGCAACCUUCAAGAGAUCUUUCUACCUGCCUUUCCAUGUCAUGAGAGGAAGAAACAAGAAUGACAAGUGUAUGACUGCCUUUGAGCUGUAGUUCCCGUUUAUUUACACAUGUGGAUCCUCGUUUUCCAAGCAUGGCUUGUUUGUUUUGAUUUCUGCUGUGCUUAUAAAUCACUUUCGGUGGGCAAGGGAGAGAGGGGAAAAUGGGUGUUGACUGAGGAAUCCCCCUUGCUUGUCUUCUUUUGAAACCGGGCAUCUCUGAAGUCCUGGUGUCAAGGGGAUCAAGAGAUGACUUCUCAGAGGUUCUAGGUGAUGCUGAGACCUUGGUGUCUCUAAACUCUGGGCAUGUGGACAGGAGGGGCUUGCGGCCGUGUCUCUGACCUGUGUGAUGUGCAGGAGGGUCUCAUUGACUCAGCGCCUGCGCGUUGUGCCUGGCUGUGCUCUCUUUUAUGCCCCCUCUAUUCUCCUCUCUCCCCCAGGGGAUUUUCAUCUCAACAACAGAGUGUCCUCACCCAGGCCUGCCUUCCGGC